AUUGUAAAUUUUAAGUCUCAGGCGUUUGCCAGCGGCACGCCAGAGAGUAUAGCCUGCGCGGAGGCCCAGAAACCAAAGAGCGAGCUCAUUCCGGGAUUGGAGAGAAGUGUGAGCAGAGGGAAGUAGAGGGAUCGGGGAGAGGAGGGGCAGGACCCACGCAUUCGGCCCUUUGCAUUCAGCUUCAUUCAACUAGGAACUUUUUCUGCAAAUCAAGGAAAGCUUCCCGGAGGAAGUGGUGCCUAAGCUGUGCUCUGAUUCACGUUUAGAAGCUGACCAGACAAAGAGAGAAUUUUGUAGCCACCUUGGCUAAUGGGAUGAGCCUCCAGCCGCCUCUUGAAGAAGUGUCCUGUGGCCAGGCGGAAAGCAGUGAGAAGCCCAACGCUGAGGACAUGACAUCCAAAGAUUACUACUUUGACUCCUACGCACACUUUGGCAUCCACGAGGAGAUGCUGAAGGACGAGGUGCGCACCCUCACUUACCGCAACUCCAUGUUUCAUAACCGGCACCUCUUCAAGGACAAGGUGGUGCUGGACGUCGGCUCGGGCACCGGCAUCCUCUGCAUGUUUGCUGCCAAGGCCGGGGCCCGCAAGGUCAUCGGGAUCGAGUGUUCCAGUAUCUCUGAUUAUGCGGUGAAGAUCGUCAAAGCCAACAAGUUAGACCACGUGGUGACCAUCAUCAAGGGGAAGGUGGAGGAGGUGGAGCUCCCAGUGGAGAAGGUGGACAUCAUCAUCAGCGAGUGGAUGGGCUACUGCCUCUUCUACGAGUCCAUGCUCAACACCGUGCUCUAUGCCCGGGACAAGUGGCUGGCGCCCGAUGGCCUCAUCUUCCCAGACCGGGCCACGCUGUAUGUGACGGCCAUCGAGGACCGGCAGUACAAAGACUACAAGAUCCACUGGUGGGAGAACGUGUAUGGCUUCGACAUGUCUUGCAUCAAAGAUGUGGCCAUUAAGGAGCCCCUAGUGGAUGUCGUGGACCCCAAACAGCUGGUCACCAACGCCUGCCUCAUAAAGGAGGUGGACAUCUAUACCGUCAAGGUGGAAGACCUGACCUUCACCUCCCCGUUCUGCCUGCAAGUGAAGCGGAAUGACUACGUGCACGCCCUGGUGGCCUACUUCAACAUCGAGUUCACACGCUGCCACAAGAGGACCGGCUUCUCCACCAGCCCCGAGUCCCCGUACACGCACUGGAAGCAGACGGUGUUCUACAUGGAGGACUACCUGACCGUGAAGACGGGCGAGGAGAUCUUCGGCACCAUCGGCAUGCGGCCCAACGCCAAGAACAACCGGGACCUGGACUUCACCAUCGACCUGGACUUCAAGGGCCAGCUGUGCGAGCUGUCCUGCUCCACCGACUACCGGAUGCGCUGAGGCCCGGCUCUCCCGCCCUGCACGAGCCCAGGGGCUGAGCGUUCCUAGGCGGUUUCGGGGCUCCCCCUUCCUCUCCCUCCCUCCCGCAGAAGGGGGUUUUAGGGGCCUGGGCUGGGGGGAUGGGGAGGGCACAUCGUGACUGUGUUUUUCAUAACUUAUGUUUUUAUAUGGUUGCAUUUACGCCAAUAAAUCCUCAGCUGGG